CUCCCGCCGGGGCCCCGGAUGCACUGAGCGGCUGCGGCGCGGCUUCCAUCCUCCCGCCCUCCUGACGCGGCCGGAGCGCAGCCCUGAGGCCCAGGGAGAACGACACAUUGGAUACAGAAGGGAGGUGAUCAUGCACCAUGGCACUGGCCCCCAGAACGUCCAGCAUCAGCUGCAGAGGUCCAGGGCCUGCCCUGGCAGCGAGGGUGAGGAGCAGCCGGCCCACCCCAACCCACCCCCGUCCCCCGCAGCUCCCUUCGCUCCCUCAGCAAGCCCGUCGGCACCCCAGUCUCCCAGUUAUCAAAUACAGCAGCUGAUGAAUAGGAGCCCUGCAACCGGGCAGAACGUGAACAUCACCCUGCAGAGCGUGGGCCCUGUCGUCGGGGGAAACCAGCAGAUCACACUGGCCCCACUGCCGCUCCCCAGCCCCACCUCUCCAGGCUUCCAGUUCAGCGCUCAGCCUCGGCGGUUUGAGCAUGGGUCUCCAUCAUACAUUCAGGUCACGUCCCCCUUGUCCCAGCAGGUCCAGACCCAGAGUCCCACGCAGCCCAGUCCGGGGCCGGGGCAGGCCUUGCAGAAUGUGCGUGCAGGUGCCCCUGGCCCUGGGCUGGGCCUCUGCAGCAGCAGCCCUACAGGGGGCUUCGUGGAUGCCAGCGUGCUGGUGAGGCAGAUCAGCUUGAGCCCCUCCAGUGGUGGACACUUUGUGUUUCAGGAUGGGUCAGGGCUCACCCAGAUCGCCCAGGGAGCCCAGGUUCAGCUCCAGCACCCGGGUACGCCCAUCACAGUCCGAGAGCGGAGACCCUCCCAGCCCCACACACAGUCAGGGGGCACCAUCCACCACCUGGGACCCCAGAGCCCUGCAGCCGCGGGUGGGGCCGGCCUGCAGCCCCUGGCCAGCCCAAGCCACAUCACCACGGCUAACUUGCCACCGCAGAUCAGCAGCAUCAUCCAGGGCCAGCUGGUUCAGCAGCAGCAGGUGCUGCAGGGGCCGCCGCUGCCCCGGCCCCUGGGCUUCGAGAGGACACCCGGCGUGCUGCUCCCCGGGGCUGGGGGCGCAGCGGGGUUUGGGAUGACGUCCCCACCCCCGCCCACCAGCCCUUCCAGGACUGCCGUGCCCCCAGGCCUUUCCAGCCUCCCACUCACGUCUGUGGGGAACACGGGAAUGAAGAAGGUUCCCAAGAAGUUAGAGGAGAUUCCCCCAGCCUCUCCGGAGAUGGCACAGAUGAGGAAGCAGUGCCUGGACUAUCAUUACCAGGAGAUGCAGGCUCUGAAGGAGGUCUUCAAGGAGUAUUUGAUUGAACUGUUUUUCUUGCAACACUUUCAAGGGAACAUGAUGGAUUUCUUAGCUUUCAAGAAGAAACAUUAUGCCCCAUUACAAGCAUAUCUUAGGCAGAAUGAUUUGGACAUUGAAGAAGAGGAGGAGGAGGAGGAAGAGGAGGAAGAAAAAUCUGAGGUUAUCAAUGACGAGCAGCAAGCCCUCGCAGGGAGCCUGGUAGCAGGGGCCGGAAGCACAGUAGAGACGGACCUGUUUAAGAGGCAGCAGGCGAUGCCCUCCACAGGUAUGGCAGAGCAGUCUAAGAGGCCUCGCCUUGAAGUGGGUCACCAAGGGGUAGUUUUCCAGCACCCAGGGGCGGACGCAGGCGUUCCUCUCCAGCAACUAAUGCCGACCGCACAAGGAGGAAUGCCCCCCACGCCGCAGGCCGCGCAGCUCGCUGGACAGAGGCAGAGUCAGCAGCAGUAUGACCCCUCCACGGGGCCUCCCGUGCAGAACGCUGCCAGCUUGCACACCCCACUGCCGCAGCUGCCCGGGAGGCUGCCCCCAGCCGGUGUUCCCACUGCAGCCCUCUCCUCUGCGCUGCAGUUUGCACAGCAGCCGCAAGUGGUAGAGGCCCAGACACAGCUCCAAAUCCCGGUGAAGACUCAGCAGCCCAAUGUUCCCAUCCCUGCACCGCCCAGCAGCCAACUCCCCAUCCCUCCCUCGCAGCCUGCACAGCUGGCCCUCCACGUUCCCACACCUGGAAAGGUGCAGGUGCAGGCCUCUCAGCUUUCCUCCCUGCCACAGAUGGUAGCAUCGACAAGGCUCCCUGUGGACCCUGCCCCGCCCUGCCCACGGCCUCUGCCCACCUCUUCUACCUCGUCCCUCGCGCCUGUGAGUGGCUCCGGCCCAGGACCCUCCCCUGCUCGAUCCUCUCCAGUAAAUAGACCUUCCUCAGCCACCAAUAAGGCACUAUCUCCAGUCACUUCCCGGACCCCAGGGGUGGUGGCAUCUGCCCCCACCAAACCACAGAGUCCUGCUCAGAAUGCCACCUCGUCCCAAGACAGUUCUCAGGAUACGCUGACAGAACAAAUAACUCUGGAGAACCAGGUGCAUCAGCGCAUUGCGGAGCUGAGGAAAGCAGGUCUGUGGUCCCAGAGGCGUCUGCCAAAGCUGCAGGAGGCCCCACGCCCCAAGUCCCACUGGGACUAUCUGCUGGAGGAGAUGCAGUGGAUGGCCACAGACUUUGCCCAGGAGAGGAGGUGGAAGGUGGCUGCUGCGAAGAAGCUCGUUAGAACUGUGGUGCGCCAUCACGAGGAGAAGCAGCUCCGUGAAGAAAGGGGGAAGAAGGAAGAGCAGAGCAGACUGAGGCGGAUAGCCGCCUCCACGGCCCGGGAGAUAGAGUGCUUUUGGUCGAAUAUUGAACAGGUUGUGGAAAUAAAACUACGAGUAGAAUUAGAAGAAAAAAGGAAGAAGGCCUUAAAUUUACAGAAAGUUUCCAGGAGAGGGAAAGAAUUGAGACCUAAAGGAUUUGACGCAUUACAGGAAAGUUCUCUGGAUUCAGGAAUGUCUGGAAGAAAAAGAAAAGCUAGCAUAUCUUUGACUGAUGACGAAGUGGACGAUGAAGAGGAAACAAUUGAAGAGGAGGAAGCAAAUGAAGGCGUUGUGGACCACCAAACAGAACUUUCUAAUUUAGCCAAGGAAGCUGAGCUGCCCCUCCUGGACCUGAUGAAGCUGUACGAAGGCGCCUUCCUGCCGAGUUCUCAGUGGCCCCGGCCGAAGCCUGAUGGGGAGGACACAAGCGGAGAGGAAGAUGCAGAUGACUGUCCAGGCGACAGGGAGAGUCGCAAGGACUUGGUUCUCAUCGACUCGCUUUUCAUCAUGGAUCAGUUCAAAGCUGCCGAGAGGAUGAAUAUCGGGAAGCCAAACGCCAAGGACAUUGCGGACGUCACUGCGGUGGCUGAAGCCAUCCUGCCGAAGGGCAGUGCUCGGGUCACAACCUCGGUCAAGUUUAAUGCUCCAUCUUUGUUGUAUGGGGCUCUCAGAGAUUAUCAGAAGAUUGGCCUGGACUGGCUGGCCAAACUUUACAGGAAGAAUCUCAAUGGCAUAUUGGCAGAUGAAGCUGGGCUGGGUAAAACAGUGCAGAUCAUUGCUUUUUUUGCCCACCUAGCUUGUAACGAAGGUAAUUGGGGCCCCCAUCUUGUUGUUGUGAGAAGUUGUAACAUACUCAAGUGGGAGCUUGAAUUGAAACGUUGGUGUCCCGGACUCAAAAUCCUCUCAUAUAUUGGCAGCCACAGAGAACUCAAAGCAAAGAGACAGGAGUGGGCCGAACCCAACAGCUUCCACGUCUGCAUCACGUCCUACACUCAGUUCUUCCGGGGCCUCACCGCCUUCACACGAGUGCGCUGGAAGUGCCUGGUCAUUGAUGAGAUGCAGCGCGUGAAGGGCAUGACCGAGAGGCACUGGGAAGCGGUUUUCACCCUGCAGAGCCAACAACGUCUGCUUCUGAUCGACUCGCCGCUGCACAAUACCUUCCUGGAGCUCUGGACCAUGGUGCACUUCCUGGUCCCAGGGAUCUCCAGGCCCUACCUGAGCUCCCCUCUGAGGGCCCCCAGUGAAGAGAGCCAGGAUUACUACCAUAAAGUGGUCAUAAGGUUACACAGGGUGACACAGCCAUUUAUUUUGAGGAGAACUAAGAGAGAUGUGGAAAAGCAACUAACAAAGAAAUAUGAGCAUGUUUUGAAGUGUCGCCUUUCUAACCGACAAAAAGCCUUAUACGAGGACGUUAUCCUGCAACCUGGCACUCAGGAGGCCUUGAAGAGCGGGCACUUUGUCAACGUCCUGAGCAUCCUUGUGCGGCUGCAGCGCAUCUGCAACCACCCUGGGCUCGUCGAGCCCCGGCACCCAGGCUCUUCCUACGUGGCGGGGCCACUGGAGUAUCCGUCCGCAUCUCUAAUCCUGAAGGCACUGGAGAGAGAUUUCUGGAAGGAAGCAGAUCUUUCUAUGUUUGAUCUCAUCGGCUUAGAAAAUAAAAUCACUCGUCACGAGGCAGAGUUGCUGUCUAAGAAAAAGAUACCGCGGAAACUCAUGGAGGAAAUCUCCACUUCAGCAGCCCCAGCAGCCCGACCAGCAGCAGCAAAGCUGAAGGCCAGCAGGUUGUUUCAGCCUGUGCAGUAUGGCCAGAAGCCCGAGGGUCGCACCGUGGCUUUCCCCAGCACUCACCCGCCCCGGACGGCAGCCCCCACCACGGCCUCUGCUGCUCCACAGGGCCCGCUUCGAGGACGGCCGCCCAUCGCCACGUUCUCUGCCAAUCCGGAGGCAAAAGCAGCAGCAGCCCCGUUUCAGACCUCUCAGGCUUCCGCCAGUGCUCCACGACACCAGCCCGCCUCGGCCUCCAGCACAGCCGCUAGCCCGGCCCAUCCUGCGAAACUGCGGGCCCAGACCACAGCACAGGCCUCCACCCCAGGCCAGCCCCCGCCCCAGCCCCAGGCCCCCUCGCACGCGGCCGGGCAGAGCGCGCUGCCUCAGAGGCUGGUGCUCCCCUCGCAGGCCCAGGCCCGCUUGCCCAGUGGAGAGGUAGUGAAAAUAGCUCAGCUGGCAUCCAUCACAGGACCACAGAGCCGCGUGGCUCAGCCAGAGACGCCGGUGACACUGCAGUUCCAGGGCAGCAAGUUCACCCUGUCACACAGCCAGCUCCGGCAGCUCACAGCGGGCCAGCCGCUGCAGCUGCAAGGCAGCGUCCUCCAGAUCGUGUCCGCCCCCGGGCAGCCCUACCUUCGAGCCCCUGGCCCUGUGGUGAUGCAGACCGUGUCUCAGGCGGGCGCUGUGCACGGCGCCCUGGGAAGCAAGCCCCCGGCCGGCGGUCCCAGCCCUGCACCCUUGACCCCACAAGUUGGCGUUCCGGGCCGCGUGGCGGUGAAUGCCUUGGCUGUAGGAGAACCCGGAACGGCCUCCAAACCAGCUUCUCCCAUUGGAGGGCCGACCCAGGAGGAAAAGACCAGACUCUUGAAAGAGCGCCUGGAUCAGAUUUAUUUAGUCAACGAGCGGCGCUGUUCUCAAGCUCCAGUCUAUGGCAGAGACUUGCUAAGGAUUUGUGCCCUGCCUAGCCAUGGAAGGGUACAGUGGCGUGGGUCCCUGGAUGGCCGUCGUGGGAAGGAGGCCGGGCCAGCGCACAGUUACACUUCAUCCUCAGAAAGUCCAAGUGAGCUGAUGUUGACGCUUUGUCGGUGUGGAGAGUCUCUGCAGGAUGUUAUUGACAGGGUGGCCUUUGUGAUUCCUCCGGUGGUGGCAGCACCCCCGUCCCUACGGGUGCCGCGGCCGCCACCCCUGUACAGCCACAGAAUGAGGAUCUUGAGGCAGGGCCUGAGAGAGCACGCUGCGCCGUACUUCCAGCAGCUGCGGCAGACCACGGCUCCACGCCUGCUGCAGUUCCCUGAGCUGAGGCUGGUGCAGUUCGACUCAGGGAAGUUGGAAGCUUUAGCUAUCUUGCUUCAGAAAUUGAAAUCUGAAGGACGUCGGGUGCUGAUUUUAUCACAGAUGAUUCUUAUGUUGGACAUUUUAGAGAUGUUCUUGAACUUCCAUUACCUCACCUAUGUAAGAAUCGAUGAAAAUGCCAGCAGUGAGCAACGGCAGGAACUGAUGAGGAGUUUCAACAGAGACAGGCGGAUUUUUUGUGCCAUUCUCUCCACUCACAGCCGUACCACAGGUAUAAACCUUGUAGAGGCGGACACCGUCGUGUUUUAUGACAAUGACCUGAAUCCAGUGAUGGAUGCCAAAGCUCAGGAGUGGUGCGAUAGGAUCGGGAGAUGCAAAGACAUCCACAUAUACAGGCUUGUGAGUGGCAAUUCCAUUGAAGAGAAAUUGUUGAAAAAUGGAACUAAAGAUCUGAUCCGAGAAGUGGCUGCUCAGGGAAAUGACUACUCCAUGGCUUUCUUAACUCAGCGAACCAUCCAGGAGCUGUUUGAAGUUUAUUCUCCCAUGGAUGAUGCUGGCUUCCCGGUCAAAGCUGAGGAGUUUGUGGUGCUUUCUCAGGAACCUUCUGUCACGGAAACCAUUGCACCCAAAAUUGCAAGACCUUUCAUAGAGGCCCUCAAGAGUAUUGAGUAUCUGGAGGAGGAUGCCCAGAAGUCCGCACAGGAGGGGGUGCUGGGACCACACACUGAUGCUCUGUCAUCAGACUCUGAGAACAUGCCGUGUGAUGAAGAACCAUCCCAAUUAGAGGAGCUAGCUGACUUCAUGGAGCAGCUUACACCAAUUGAAAAAUAUGCUUUAAAUUACCUGGAAUUAUUCCAUACUUCUAUUGAGCAAGAAAAGGAGAGAAACAGUGAGGACGCAGUGAUGACUGCAGUGAGGGCAUGGGAGUUCUGGAACCUGAAGACCCUGCAGGAGAGGGAGGCCCGGCUGCGGCUGGAGCAGGAGGAGGCGGAGCUCCUGACCUACACGCGAGAGGAUGCCUACAGCAUGGAGUAUGUCUACGAAGAUGUCGAUGGGCAGACAGAAGUCAUGCCGCUCUGGACCCCACCCACCCCGCCGCAGGACGACAGCGACAUCUACCUCGACUCGGUCAUGUGUCUCAUGUAUGAAGCCACUCCCAUCCCAGAGGCUAAGCUGCCCCCUGUGUACGUGAGGAAGGAGCGGAAGCGACACAAAACAGACCCCUCAGCUGCAGGCAGGAAGAAGAAGCAGCGUCACGGGGAGGCGGUCGUCCCUCCUCGGUCCCUGUUUGACCGCGCAACACCAGGACUUCUGAAAAUUCGCAGAGAGGGCAAGGAGCAGAAGAAGAAUAUUCUGCUGAAGCAGCAGGUGCCAUUCGCCAAGCCCCUGCCAACUUUUGCCAAACCCACAGCUGAGCCUGGUCAAGACAACCCCGAGUGGCUCAUCAGUGAGGACUGGGCGCUGCUGCAGGCUGUAAAGCAGUUACUGGAGCUGCCUUUGAACCUCACAAUCGUGUCACCUGCUCACACACCUAAUUGGGAUCUUGUCAGUGACGUUGUUAACUCCUGUAGCCGAAUCUACCGCUCUUCCAAACAGUGCCGGAAUCGCUACGAGAAUGUCAUCAUUCCACGAGAGGAGGGGAAGAGUAAAAACAACCGUCCUCUCCGUACGAGCCAGAUCUAUGCCCAGGAUGAGAAUGCCACACACACCCAGCUGUACACGAGCCACUUUGACUUAAUGAAAAUGACUGCUGGCAAGAGGAGUCCCCCAAUCAAACCUCUGCUUGGCAUGAAUCCCUUUCAGAAGAACCCCAAGCACGCGUCUGUGUUGGCAGAAAGUGGAAUCAACUAUGACAAGCCGCUGCCUCCCAUCCAGGUGGCAUCUCUCCGUGCAGAGCGAAUCGCAAAAGAGAAAAAGGCUCUGGCUGAUCAGCAGAAGGCACAGCAGCCGGCCGUGGCCCAGCCACCCCCGCCCCAGCCGCAGCCCCCACCACCCCCGCAGCAGCCACCGCCACCGCUGCCACAACCACAGGCAGCGGGCAGCCAGCCGCCAGCAGGGCCACCAGCUGUCCAGCCCCAACCCCAGCCACAGCCCCAGACCCAGCCACAGCCUGUGCAGGCCCCAGCGAAGGCGCAGCCCGCAAUCACGACGGGGGGCAGUGCAGCCGUACUGGCAGGAACCAUUAAAACAUCAGUUACUGGGACGAGCAUGCCCACUGGUGCCGUGAGUGGAAAUGUGAUCGUGAACACCAUCGCAGGGGUCCCAGCUGCCACCUUCCAGUCCAUCAACAAGCGCCUGGCGUCGCCAGUGGCUCCUGGGGCCUUGACUACGCCGGGAGGCUCUGCUCCCGCCCAGGUGGUGCACACCCAGCCCCCGCCACGGGCAGUCGGCUCCCCAGCCACGGCGACCCCUGACCUGGUGUCCAUGGCAACGACUCAGGGUGUUCGAGCGGUCACUUCUGUGACAGCCUCGGCCGUGGUCACUACCAACCUGACCCCAGUGCAGACCCCGGCACGGUCUUUGGUGCCCCAAGUGUCCCAAGCCACAGGAGUUCAGCUCCCUGGAAAAACCAUCACACCUGCACAUUUCCAGCUUCUCAGGCAGCAGCAGCAGCAGCAGCAACAACAGCAGCAGCAGCAGCAGCAGCAGCAGCAGCAGCAGCAGCAGCAACAGCAGCAGCAGCAACAGACGACGACGACCUCUCAGGUGCAAGUUCCACAGAUCCAGGGCCAGGCCCAGUCCCCAGCACAGAUCAAAGCUGUGGGCAAGCUGACGCCGGAACACCUCAUCAAAAUGCAGAAGCAGAAACUGCAGAUGCCCCCGCAGCCCCCACCGCCACAGGCCCAGUCUGCGCCCCCGCAGCCAACAGCCCAAGUGCAAGUGCAGACCUCGCAGCCGCCGCAGCAGCAGAGCCCCCAGCUCACGACGGUCACGGCCCCAAGGCCUGGUGCCCUGCUGACGGGCACCACCGUGGCCAACCUCCAGGUGGCCCGGCUCACCCGGGUUCCCACUUCUCAGCUGCAGGCGCAAGGGCAGAUGCAGACCCAGGCACCCCAGCCAGCCCAGGUGGCCUUGGCGAAGCCUCCGGUGGUGUCCGUCCCGGCAGCUGUGGUCUCCUCACCGGGAGUCACCACCCUGCCCAUGAACGUCGCGGGGAUCAGCGUGGCGAUCGGUCAGCCACAGAAGGCAGCAGGACAGACCGUGGUGGCCCAGCCCGUGCACAUGCAGCAGCUGCUGAAGCUGAAGCAGCAGGCCGUCCAGCAGCAGAAGGCCAUCCAGCCCCAGGCUGCACAGGGCCCGGCAGCCGUCCAGCAGAAGAUCACCGCACAGCAGAUCACCACCCCUGGCGCGCAGCAGAAGGUUGCCUACGCCGCGCAGCCGGCCCUUAAGACCCAGUUUCUUACCACACCCAUCUCCCAGGCCCAGAAACUGGCCGGGGCCCAGCAAGUGCAGACCCAGAUCCAGGUUGCAAAACUUCCUCAAGUUGUUCAACAGCAAACACCCGUGGCCAGCAUCCAGCAAGUUGCCUCUGCUUCCCAGCAGGCUUCUCCACAGACUGUGGCGCUCACGCAGGCGACGGCGGCCGGGCAGCAGGUGCAGAUGAUCCCUGCAGUGACCGCGACUGCCCAGGUGGUUCAGCAGAAACUCAUUCAGCAGCAGGUGGUGACCACGGCGUCGGCCCCGCUCCAGACUCCAGGCGCUCCCAACCCAGCCCAGGUGCCCGCCAGCUCCGACAGCCCAAGCCAGCAGCCCAAGUUACAGAUGAGGGUCCCUGCUGUCAGGCUAAAGACACCUACUAAGCCUCCGUGCCAGUAGUCAGGGCAGCAGGGCUGCCUCUCAUCUAAAGCAAAACUACCUUCCUCACAGAAAACGCUUUAUUAGUGAACCUUGGGACCAUGUCACGCAAGAGAUUCAGCACUGGGAAAGAUAUAAUUGAAACAAAAUAGUGUAAUCAUUUUAUUAAAAUGCAUCCCACACUGCAGGACAAAUGGUCCUUAUGGAGUGCCGCGUUCUCUGUACUACGUGGCUCAUGGAAAAAGUGACAACAUGGCUUCCUCUAAAUCAUUUCACCUUUCAGUCCCCACCCGCACCCGUCCCCUAGAGCCAUAGUACUGUGUUCUGAAAGCCAUUUAGAAUUUCUUUGUGAGCAUGUAGUGCUUUGCACGCCACAGAAGCCGUCUGCCGUGUGUGAGGAGCAUACAAUGGACUUUCUAAAGAUAAGGCGUGGGCUUCCACAGUGUCUGCCAGAGUUUAGUUCUUUAUACCUUACUGAAAAAUGCCUCGUGGUCUUCGCAGAGGGGAAGGCCUGUCUAAAGUCAAUCAUCCGAGAUGGGUUUUCCAUUCCAAAGAAAGGCAAUAUGGUUCCUUCCUUCCCUCCUAAAAUAUGACUUAACUUUUAAGAGAAAUGUUCUGACACCCACCUAAACACACAAGGCACGUUCCUGGCCUGUGUUCAAGGGAAAUGAUCAGUCAUUGCAUUGUUAUUCCAAAGAGCAGCCAACAGUGGCCUCCCCCAGGCCCUACCCUGCAAUGGGAUUCGCUUUCAUUUAAUGGAAACUUCUGGGACUGAUGCCCAACUCAGUGCACUCAAGACGCAUCUCCAGUUUUCGGGGGAAGCUGGUAUUUGACAUAGUGUGUUAAACAGCUCCUGAGAACCUUUGGGACACUCUGCCAUGGCUGGCGUGAGGCCCAGAGGACCACGCAGAGGCAAUGGUAGUACAGAUGUCACAGCUGAGGGUACGAUGAGGCCUGGGCUCAGUGAGCCAGGACGAAUGUGACAGACACCCCUUGCUGCCACAGUCAGCCCUUUGACGAAGGUGGGCUGGUGAUUCUGGAAGUAUUGGCUAUAGCGGUGGGCCCAGUCAACUCUUCCUUGUGGACUUACGACAGCAGAUUUUCUCUAGGAUAAGCUUGUGUGGUUCUGCCAGUGAAGCAGAGAACCACCUGUGCUGUUGUGGAAGGCGUGCCGUUGAGGGGGAAAACGAAGCCCAGUAUUUGCUACUGUUUUUCCUUUUUUUACUAUGACAGGAAAAUAAAUGCAAUUUUAGUGGAAUUGAUUGACAGUGUCUCCUUACUUUGAAGUUUUCACCAAAGCAAAAAGGUCCAUAUCCAAUAGUAUCCUUUGUGCUGUGGCUUGAUUUUGGCCUAUUUUACAUUAUUUGGUCCAGGAAAUUAGGUUAUAUUAGGUUUUUUGUAUACUAAAAAUCAGUUAUGGCACAAUAAAGAUUUUCUGUUUUUAAAUUGUAUUUCAUCUGCUUCCUCCCCAUUCUCUCACUUUAAGUGACAUUGAGGAAGGUAUUCUGUCCCACAGGUUUCUGUGGACAGCGAUACAGCAGGAGUCAGUGAAAUCAACUGGGGAGCUCACUUGAGCUCUUGAUAAGAAAUGUGGAGAAAAGUAAAAACCAAGCUUUGAAGAAACAGAAGAAAUUAAUCUUUUAGUUAGUUGAACAUACCAAAGCAGAGGACUGGAAUCUGUUUGUUCUAACCAACCCGUUCUCCCUGGCUUGGCACGUGCCGUGAGAGCGCAGCUUGCCGGAGGGAGGGCCGCUGUGUGCGCCUCACAUCUGGCUCCCAGUGGAAACUUUUACUCCUCCUCAUCCGCAGAUGUGAUAGAACUGAAGUAUCUAGGAAUUCUGCCUUUGUCAUUUGUUUUAAUUUGUGUGCCCUGUUCAUUUUUUUUGUCUUUCCCAAAUCUUGGUAGUCUCCUUAUAGUUGAAGAUAAAAUGUUGAGUGCACUUAUUUUAGAAUAUCCUAGACAUAACUGUCUAAGUAAAAGCGCUCUAUUAAUCUAAAACACUACAAGAGAAUUUAACACCAUCUCUCAAAUGCUUUUUUGGAGAGCUUAAUGGGAUUCUGAAUAUUUGCAAUGUGGAGUUUCCGCCCCGAUCUCACGUCAGUGAGGGUCUCCUGUCUCUCAAGUGUGUUUCCUUUGGCUGUUCCCUAAUACAAAACACGGACAUAUUUUUACUCGUAGCACUCAAUUUAGUAACUUCUAGAUGCUACCGUUGACCUGAGUUAAAUUCAUUUAGUCGUGUACGUAAAAACUCUCCUUUUAGUGUGUUAUUUUCUUGGCCUUCCCUUUUAAAGGUUAAAGUUUCUAACCUAAGAAUUAAGUACGCGUUCAGGAAGCUGUUGUCUAGGCCUUCCCCUUGUGAAUCUGGGUUCAUUCCAAUACGGCAAGUAAGAGUUGGAAACUUUGAGAACACAGACUAUAAAGGCAGCAGCCCGAACACUGUCAGACUCUAAUUGGCGACCCUGGGAAACAGUUGCCCUGCUAUUCUUUAAAGAAAGACGUUUAUUCUGAUGAUAAAAACAGUUAGCCAGACUGUUUUUAAAGCACCUGGCGGGAAGCAGAAGGUUGGAUCCAAGCCCUUGUUCAGAUUUGGUGCCUGAUAAGACAGGGGUUUCUCUUUUUGUGACCUUUAUUAUUAUUAUUUUGUUAACUGUUGUAACCAGUUAGCUGUUGUGUUUUAAGAUAGAAAGGAACAAGACUAAAAUUGUAAAUACUUUGUAAACAUCAGCAUUUGUACUUGAAUAGUAGGAUUUUAAAGGGCAUUGAUAGCAUACCAAACAAAAGGCAAAAUAAAGUGACCUUUUUAUAUA